AGGAGAGGCCACCGGGACCGCGAGCGGCAGCUGGGGAGGGGGCCGCGGAGCCCGAGCGGGAGCAAAACAGCUGAUCUGGUUUUCCUUUAAAGCGAGAGAAAAUGGAAGUCGGGUAGCGGCGACUGCGGCGCUGCGGGCUGGCGGAGCGGAGCGGCGCGGCGCGGCAGAGUUCUCAGGCGCUGUGGUCUCACCUUCCACUGGGGCAACAAUGGGCCAUUUCCAGCAGGGACGGCGCAGUGUUGGCCUGCAUGCCUGACUGCCACACACCUCCAGAAUCAGGUGUCUGAAAAGUGGCAGUGACGAAAGAAGAGACUCUCCCGGCCGAGGCCCCAGUGCAUGGAGAGAAGGAAGAAAUCAAUUUCCUAAUUGGUACCAUAUACAUCAGAUGGAUGGUUUCUAGUGUGCUUCCAAACCCCACCUCGGCUGAGUGUUGGGCAGCACUUCUACAUGAUCCUAUGACUCUUGAUAUGGACGCAGUCCUGUCAGACUUUGUUCGGUCCACGGGGGCAGAACCUGGUCUGGCCAGAGACCUGCUGGAAGGCAAAAACUGGGACCUGACAGCCGCUCUGAGCGACUAUGAGCAGCUCCGCCAGGUGCACACAGCCAAUCUGCCACAUGUGUUCAAUGAAGGGCGGGGUCCCAAGCAGCCAGAGCGAGAGCCACAGCCCGGGCACAAGGUGGAGCGACCCUGCCUGCAGAGGCAGGACGACAUUGCCCAAGAAAAGCGGCUUUCCCGGGGGAUUUCCCACGCCAGCUCAGCCAUCGUCUCCCUGGCCCGGUCCCACGUGGCAAGUGAAUGCAACAACGAGCAGUUCCCCCUGGAGAUGCCAAUCUACACAUUCCAGUUGCCAGACCUGAGCGUGUACAGCGAGGAUUUCAGGAGCUUCAUCGAGCGGGACUUGAUCGAGCAGGCAACAAUGGUGGCUUUGGAGCAGGCAGGUCGCCUGAACUGGUGGUCCACUGUGUGCACGAGCUGUAAACGGCUUCUUCCUCUGGCCACAACAGGGGAUGGGAACUGCCUUUUACAUGCUGCUUCACUGGGAAUGUGGGGGUUUCACGACCGGGACCUGGUGUUACGGAAAGCUCUCUAUACCAUGAUGAGGACGGGAGCUGAGAGGGAAGCCCUGAAGCGGAGGUGGAGGUGGCAGCAGACGCAGCAGAAUAAGGAGGAGGAGUGGGAGCGGGAGUGGACGGAGCUGCUGAAGCUGGCCUCCAGCGAGCCGCGCACACACUUCAGCAAGAAUGGCGGCACGGGCGGGGGUGUGGACAACUCUGAGGACCCCGUGUACGAGAGCCUGGAAGAGUUCCACGUUUUUGUCCUAGCCCAUAUAUUAAGAAGGCCCAUCGUUGUUGUGGCAGAUACAAUGUUAAGAGACUCAGGUGGAGAAGCGUUCGCACCCAUCCCAUUCGGAGGGAUCUACCUGCCCUUGGAGGUCCCUCCCAACAGAUGCCACUGCUCGCCUCUGGUUCUGGCCUAUGAUCAAGCCCAUUUCUCUGCCCUUGUGUCCAUGGAACAGAGAGACCAGCAAAGAGAACAAGCCGUGAUCCCCCUGACGGAUUCUGAGCACAAGCUGCUGCCUCUGCACUUUGCAGUGGACCCUGGCAAGGACUGGGAGUGGGGGAAAGACGACAACGAUAACGCCCGGCUGGCCCACCUUAUCCUGUCGCUAGAAGCCAAGCUGAACCUUCUGCACAGCUACAUGAACGUGACGUGGAUCCGGAUCCCCUCCGAGACACGGGCGCCCCUGGCACAGCCGGAGUCUCCCACGGCCUCGGCAGGGGAGGACGUGCAGUCCCUGGCCGACUCGCUGGACUCGGACCGCGAUUCGGUGUGCAGCAAUUCUAACAGCAAUAACGGCAAGAACGGCAAGGACAAGGAGAAGGAGAAGCAGCGCAAGGAGAAGGACAAGACGCGCGCCGACUCCGUGGCCAACAAGCUGGGCAGCUUCAGCAAGACGCUGGGCAUCAAGCUGAAGAAAAACAUGGGCGGCCUCGGCGGCCUGGUGCACGGCAAGAUGGGCCGCGCCAACUCCGCCAAUGGCAAGAACGGGGACUCGGCCGAGCGGGGCAAGGAGAAGAAGGCCAAGUCGCGCAAGGGCAGCAAGGAGGAGUCUGGUGCGUCGGCCAGCACGUCGCCGUCGGAAAAGACCACGCCGUCGCCCACAGACAAGGCAGCGGGCGCGUCGCCGGCGGAGAAGGGCGGUGGGCCGCGGGGCGACGCCUGGAAGUACAGCACGGAUGUGAAGCUGAGCCUCAACAUCCUGCGCGCCGCCAUGCAGGGGGAGCGCAAGUUCAUCUUCGCCGGCCUGCUGCUCACCAGCCACCGGCACCAGUUCCACGAGGAGAUGAUCGGCUACUACCUGACGAGCGCGCAGGAGCGCUUCAGCGCCGAGCAGGAGCAGCGGCGCCGCGACGCCGCUACUGCGGCCGCCGCUGCCGCCGCCGCCGCCGCCGCCACGGCCAAGCGGCCGCCGCGCAGACCGGAGACGGAGGGCGUGCCGGUCCCGGAGCGCGCCUCUCCGGGCCCACCCACGCAGCUGGUGCUCAAGCUCAAGGAGCGGCCGAGCCCCGGGCCCGCGGCAGGGCGUGCGGCGCGGGCGGCGGCGGGCGGCACGGCCUCCCCGGGGGGAGGCGCGCGGCGUGCGAGCGCCAGCGGACCAGUGCCUGGCCGCAGCCCCCCGGCGCCAGCGCGCCAGAGCGUCAUCCACGUGCAGGCGUCGGGCGCGCGGGACGAGGCGUGCGCGCCGGCCGUGGGGGCGCUGCGGCCGUGCGCCACGUACCCGCAGCAGAACCGCUCGCUGUCGUCGCAGAGCUACAGCCCGGCGCGCGCCGCCGCCCUGCGCACCGUCAACACGGUCGAGUCGCUGGCGCGCGCGGUGCCCGGGGCCCUACCGGGCGCGGCGGGGACGGCGGGGGCGGCCGAGCACAAGUCGCAGACCUACACCAACGGCUUCGGCGCCCUGCGCGACGGCCUGGAGUUCGCCGACGCCGACGCGCCGACCGCGCGCUCGAACGGUGAGUGCGGCCGUGGCGGCCCGGGGCCGGUGCAGCGGCGCUGCCAGCGCGAGAACUGUGCGUUCUACGGGCGCGCCGAGACCGAGCACUACUGCUCCUACUGCUACCGCGAGGAGCUGCGGCGGCGGCGCGAGGCGCGCGGGGCCCGGCCCUGAGCGGCGCGGCGCGGCGCGGGCGGCGAGGUUCUACCUUCGAGGAUUUCUUUUCCAUUGUGUCGGUGUCUUUUUUACAUGCCCUGGUCCACCGGAAGGCCGGCGCCUCCUCUGUCAGUGCCGUGUACGUGUUUGGUCAAACGUUCCUAAUGGUGCCUGAACCUACACUGACGCCACUCAGGUAGUAGACGGAUAGGAAACAAGUCAUACUGUUGGAAGUGGGUGUGCUAGCCUAGCAUCUGCCUCGUACCUGUGGAAACUCAAUAGCCAUUGCAAGAGUAUUUUUGUUCCUCAGUAAGAGAAAUAAAGAAAUUCGCAGCCCUUUGUUUUAAGAAGGGAGUGUUUUACAUGCUUUUUUUGCUUUUUUUUUUUUCUCCUACCCUAGCGAUGACCUCUUCCAGGUAGCGGUCCCUUGUGCGCGGUUGGUAGUACCCAGGGCUUAGAGCGAGCGCGCACCCGGGGCUGCGGUGGAGGCUCCUCUGUGAGCUCUACCUGCCUCCCAUCCCGAGGCCUAGGAGAAGGCGGGUACCUGGCCGCCAGCUGACGCCCUGGUGGUCACUGUGGCCCUUUAGAAACACACAGCUCCAUUUCAUAAGCAAAACCUCCUCCCCCAGCCCCGGCUCAAGCACCAUUCACACUGCCAUCCAAGCCGCGGGCGGCCGUGGAAAGGGCACUGGACCACCCGUCUCGCGGGCGCCGUGAGGUACAGCGAUGGCUCCCAGUGCCGGGCAGUUCAGGUGACAGGAGCUUUCCAAAGACACCUAGGGUCCAAAAAGCAGGGUUCCCAUCUCACAAUUUGGAUUUGCUCAUAGAGGAGCAGAUAGGACAGGCUGCUCACAUUUCUCCUUUGAAGGCACUUCCACAGUGGACUGUCGCUGGCGGGCCCCUGGGCGGUGACCAUCGGUGCCCCGGGAGACAGCGAGGAAUUGACCCUUUGGUCACUGUGUAAGCCCCCACUAGGCUGCUGCUCUUUCCAAAGGGAAGGGGCUGGGGGAACCAGGAAGGAAGCCCACCCCCACACCUGCAUCUGUCUGGGUUCAGCCAGGUAAAGGGACUCACUGUGAUCGUGGCCCCUCCACGGGGCAGGACGACCCUGCCUCCGUCUCGUGACACAAUGAGGGAGCAGCCCGAUCCCUGAGCGGUCUCUUUUUUGGUGCCUCCUACAUUUCUUGAGGAAAAAAAAAAUGUGUCCUUAGCUACCCUGUUUUGAGCAGCAAUAUGCAGCCUCUUCCUUCCAAGAUUACCUCCGGAGAACACCGUUCUUGGCCAAGGACACUGAGGAGCUAAAUCUGCCUCACUAAGGAACGAGCUUGUUUCCAAGAAAUGAGGAUAAGAUGGGUAAAAUCCUCACUAACAAAGAAUACUAUAAAACCUGUGAGAGCCUUAGAAUAGCUUCUAAUAAUCCUAGGACAGGAGAAAGCGCCUGGCUUUGCUGUGAGUGUAUCCUCAGAAAAAGCAGGAGGUCGACCAUCUCUUCACUGGAGCCAGCUUCUCCUCUAGAAACGAUGCUUUUUUCCCUAACUAAAGAGCAGCAAAAACAAAAAAAAAGGGGGGGCGAGGGGAUUUUUUUUACUUGUUUGAGAAAUUAUAAUAAAAUAAUUGAGUAUCUCCUGUGAGUAAUGCCUUUUUGUUUUUAAUUAUUCCACAGCAGGUGGAGUUUUCAGUAAUUUGUUCAAGUUUUGCAUAAGUGGUUCCUUAAAUCAAAAAUUAUUUAUUAAAUAGGAUCUUUAAGAAAUUUUUUGAAAGUUUUACUUUUCCUGCUGAACAAUAUUUUCAAUGUGUGGUAAUUACUGUACUAACAUCCAUGUCCCUAAUAUUACUGGGGUUUCUUUUAUUACUCAGAAAACAAAAGUGGUUUUUUAAAAAUCUCAUGGAGAGGGUCUGUGGCAGCUUUCUGGACUGAUUCUUCGUGUCACGCUGAGCAGCUGCUUUGGCAUCCAAAGCUGUGGGAUCACAGAAAGUGUUGCUUCAGGUGUGGAUGCCAGCCACUCCUCAUGCUCGUCACUCUUAAAAGAUUGAGACACCCAACCUUAAAAAUGCUCCAAUAAUCCAUUCAGAAACCAAACUCAUAUGCACAAGAUGUCAAGGAGGCAUAAAGUCAAUUCUUGCUUGUUUUUUUCAUUUCUUAAUGUAAAAACAGCCAACCAGAAAUUUCUAAAACUGGCUAUGCUAAUUCAGAUAUUUUCUUUCUCACGCUAUCUGCCAGGUUUGUCUAAUUUAAAAAAUAAAAAAAUAAAACAGAAUAAAAACCGUCCAUUGUAAUAGAGGAAAACCUUCCAAACCAGGCAGAGUACGUAAUUAUCAAAACACCAGGACCUAUUCUACCCUUGCAUUUCCAAGUUACCUCCACCCAUCACCAUCUGAUGACAGAUGUGCCCUAAAUAAGAGCCUGAGAUAAAGCCACUGGCUGCAUCCUGCACCCCAGCUUCUCAAUGUGGUAACGAGGCGCCAGACGCCUGUAGACACCUGCUCCAGGCUGAUACAUUACCACUCAGUCCACAUGACUUAGGAAUAGCCAUUUCCUUUUGUGAGAGAGCUGGAUCCAUCCUUCCUCUAAACAGUAUUAAAAAUGCAAAAGGGAGAGAGCGGAUGGUCAUAUUAAAUGUGCUAGUCCCGUGCACCGACAGCAUGCUCCUUGAGAAGAGGCGUGUAGACCUCGUCCCUGGCCAGAGACCAACUUCAGCAGGCUGGCCAGAAACUAUUAAAAACUGUGUUGACUGCAUGUGGGCCAAGGGCUUCCCUCGUGUUCCAUGGCGUGAGGGCCCUUUGUGGAGCAGGGAGAAAGGGAAGAAGGUGAGUCCUACCGGGGUGCAUGGCCCUGCUGCCCUAGCUGACCCUGCCUGAGAGCAGCCUUCCCCACCUGAUCUGGCCACACUUCCCUUUCUAGGAAGGACAGGUGUCUCCAAGGGACUGCAGGUUUCCAGAGGAUCCCAGAUACUUCUAAACCCCUGCGAAGGUUAUUUCAGAAAUUUACUUUACAUUUCCUGCACAUUUGUUAUCUGGGUAAAUGAUUUUUUUAAAAUAUUGUUAAGGGAAGGUGUUUUUCAGUGUAUUCUGUUGGUAGACUUUAUGCUGUGUUACGUUGAAAUUUUACAAGCCAAGUUUAAACUGUACUAUAAAAAUUAUUUUUGUAUUAUUUUCAGAACAUGCCACAGAGCAAUAUUUUGCACCCGUUAUUGCCACAGGGUUGUCCCUUGGAAGGGUAACUGGAGGUGGGAAGGAGCUCCACUGUGGGCUCCGGGGGGUUAAACGCUUUUUGCUGCUUGUUCAAAUACCUUCUGAAAGUGGGAAUGUAUCAGUGUCUUUUUUUAUUGAAAGCUUGAUUUCCUUUUUUCUGUUCAUGGAUUUUGGUACUGCACCUUUCCUCUUAAAUGAAUACUUUGUAUUCACUAAAUUACUGUGGACCUUUUCAUACCUAUUACCACCCAGUGGCAUUUGAAUCUAUUUACAAAUCGAAUGUUUUCCCAAAUGAUUUAAUUUACUACUUCUCGUAGCUUACUGUCAAGAAUUGGGGGUGCUGAAGAUAAAAGGACUCUCCAUGCCCCCCAGGUGCACACCUCAGGGUGUGGACAUCCUCCAUGCAGAGCCCGCCCUGUCUCUGGGGAGGGGUCAUGGGCCCAUCACCCCCCCCCCCCACUUAGUGUCCACAAACUUAUUUUGCGAACUAUUCUACUUUGCAAAAAUAAACUUAAAAUAUACUUCCCAUUGGUUAAGAUAAAAGGGCUGUACUUAUCAGUGGUGGGAAAUUUGUACAAGAAAAAACAGACUUUUCCAAAUCCAUGUGUGUAAGUUCCAUUCCAUGUGAGUCUUUUAUUUACGAAGAGACCUGGAGUAAAAGCUGAAGGCAUCUACUGUAUGUUUGGGGCUCCUUUCUUUAUGGCCAUGAUUUUUUUUCUCCUCAUCUUGGUGUGGACUUUAAAAUUAAGUACCCCCAGUGUUCUGUCCUUUUUCUUUCCUCAGUGCUUCUAAUAGAUAAGAAGAAAUGUGUUUCUGUGGCUGAGCAAGCCCUGCUGGGCCAGACAGACCUUACCAGCCCUGGCUUCAUCCUCGCUGGGCUGCAGAGGCGGCCCCUGCUCUAGUUGAGUCCGGUUCUGCUGCCAGCUGAGGACAGACACACCGUAUGAAGGGCCUAGAGGUGGCUGGCAUGCCAGGGAGCAGGUGGCCCCUUCCAAAACGCCUUAAAGUGGUGGCUCUCUAGAGAUCUGAGGCACCACCUUCCCAUUUACUCCUGACUCUAAACUCUAGCUGGCCUGUUUUAGUGUGGCUGGCCGGGGCAGUGACCAGCGCUCAGCUUUGUUCUUGUUUAAUUCAAGUCCACCCUGUUGCCCGUGUCCUCUCCACAGCUCUGGGUCUGUUGGCCCGGAGUGUAUUUCUGCCAGUGCUGCCUCACUGACUCGGGAGUGGGUCCUGGGUAGUUCACGAUAGAGAGGCCAGCACACGCCAUGGGGAGAGCCCCCCACGCUCACCCCAGGAGGCCCUGCGGCACAUCCAGGCUGGACCACUCUGCAAGCUUCUGUCACAAAAGACAGCUCCGGGCACUGUGCAAAUUGGCCUGUUAGCAGUUAUGCAGGUCCCUUCUUUGCCAAAAGAUCUAUUAUUCCUCCCCACUGCACCCCCAGCAGAAAAGAGCGAGGGAGAUGCCCUGCAGGGACCCCUUGGGAACAACAGUUAUGUGCAGUCUGUGCAGUAUGAAGAACUUGGCCCCACCAGGCUGAGCCGAAGACACACGUAGUUGCAGAGUAGCACUGAAGCCAUCAUCUCCAACCAUGCUAGUAAUGUUACUGUUUCUAUUUAUUUUGCCAAAUGAUUUGUUGAAAAUUGCAUUUUUGCUAUUUUAAUCUUGCCAAAAAAGGGGGCCUCACUAAUCCUAAUUAUGUACAUACAGAAUGAUGCACAUUGCUUGCAUCUUUUUAUUCCUCCCAAAGAGCAUAUCAAGGAUAUAUAUAUACAUAAUUUGUUAGUUUAACAUAAGGCGAAGAGUACCAUUUGGUUUUAAGAGUAAAUAUAGGCUGAAUUUAUUCAAGACCAAAGCAACCUAUUUAAUGAGGACAAAUGAGUGAAACCAGCUGUUUUAGAAUUUAUCUGCAGACACUGGAGUGCUCCUUUAAACGAAGAAACAGCCUCCCAUGGCAGAGGAAAAGCCAGGUCCUUACAAAGGCCUCUCCCAUCCCAGUACUUCUUCUGCCUGCUGCUCUGCCCUGGGACGUAGGCCUUCCUGCCGUUUCUAGUCACAGGCACCCUCCUGCCUCAGGGCCUUUGCACAUGCCAUUCCUUCUACCUGAACAUUCUUCCCCAGAGAGCCACAUGGUUCACCCCUCACUACCUGCCAGUCUUUGCUCCAAUGUCACCUUUCAACGAGGCCUUCCCUGACUUAUUUAAAAGGACAACACACCCCACCCUCCCUCCCUACCCACCUCUCUGCAUCUUCUUCUUGUGCACCUAUCACCAUCUGAGUGCUGCAGAUGUUAAUCAUUCAUCCAUUUAUUUGAUUCUCGCCUCCCCAUCUCCCAUAGACUGUAAGCUCCAUGUGGGCAGGAACUUUUAUAUGUCUUGCUCAUUGCUGUAUCCUGGUGCCUACAACAGUGCCUGACACAUAUUAGGCACUGGAUAAGUAUUUAUUGAAAAAAGGAAAUUAAAUCAGUAAAUUGAAAACUAUUAAGAGGCCAGAAAAUGUCAAUUUCAGCUUUCAUCAAAUCUAGGUUCUAUUAUUGUGAGAACUUUAGCUGACCCAGUGACCUGGCUCCUAUGGGUACAAGAUGGUUAGAUACACCGGGCAGCAGCGGUGGCUUCUGUUCACAGACAAGUGAAUGCCUGCCCUGCCGCUAGCCCCACCUCACAAAUAUGAGGCUCACUGUUCGCAGGGGAGCAUUUUGGAACCAGCUGGGAUGAAGACAGUUUUCUGCAGGUAGCUUUUGUAGCCAGAUGCACAGUAGUGGGUUCCCAUCACUCCAUGAGGUCACUGUAGACCUGGACCAUUCCAGAGAAUCCUUUGUAAUCAGUCUUUAGGUGUCUCCCAGUCCUUCCCAGUUCAACACGGGUGGCAGCAGAUGGCCCAGCCCAGGGAAAGUCCACCUGACCAUUAGAAGGACUCAUCCUCCAGCCACCAAAGCAAGGCUGCAGAGGAAGAGGAGCUUGUCACAAACAUUAACCGGCUCAGGGCUGGGUAACUGCAUUGACAAAUUUGGAAGCAGCAGGGCCAGAGAGCCAAGGCCCCCGGGUAUCCCCAUUGGCCACUGGUGGAGGUGCACUGGAAGGUCAGGGCCUUGACACCACAGAGCCAAGCAACACACACCUCCUUGGGCCCAGGCCCCAGCACGGUGGCCCUCCAGUGCUGGCAGGUGGCCUCACCCACAGCAGGGGAGGCGUGGGUCCUCCAAUGACCUUCCUGCCCCUGCCAGAUGAUUUUCACAACUACCUAACUUUGGUGUUUACUUCUAGGUCCUUUGGCCAAAUGCGUUUUCUUCUAAGAGUUGUUGGCAAAAUACUGUUACAAGCUUCUUAUGGGACUUUUGUCCUACUGUGGCCUGGUUAAAGGCUUUGUCCUCCUGUUUAAUCCACUUCCGUGGUUUUGCUGUCAUUUCUCUUGAUGCCAUAUUUUCAGGUCCCUCGUGGGAGGGGGCAUAAGGUCUCCAUCGUGAUGCCCUCUCUGCAGCUGUCCAGCCAGCAGUGAGUGGGCCCACACAUGUGCAUUCCUGUGCUUGAAUUGCCAAAUAAACAGUGUCCCUUUCAUUGCUGCCCAAACAGACUGGAAGCCUGCUCCUGCCAGCACUCAGGGAGGGAGUGUGUGCUUCCCAAGAGCCUGCCCCCUUGGCCCAUGCAAACUUUCUCCAUGGCAGGUGUCCGUGAAGGUCUCCCAGGCCCUAUGGGCUGUCCAGCUCUUUGCACACAUUCUUCCCGCUUGCAGGAAUGGAAUCCAAACACCUGAUACGGAAUGAUGACUUGGCAGUGGGGAGUGGGGCAGCUUGUCUCCGCUAACUUAGGACCAAAACUAGGAAACUCACCAUGAGCAUGUGUUGGAGAUCAGCUGUGGCCUCCAGCCCCUGUACACACAGAGGCAAGCCCCACCUCUGACAGAGCCAGUCACCGUUCAGUAGGAGCUUGUCUUCCCUGGGCCCCCAGGUGGGAAAGGCUGGGCUCUUAGUCCUACAAGUAAAGGCGCUGUUAGGAGCAAGGAGCAGGCUUAGCUGGGUCCACAGAGGGACUAAGCUCCUUAGUGACCUGUUACUGCCUCAUCUACGGAGUUUGAACUCCAUUCACCAUCACCUUUGAGAAUUUGGCCUUGUUUUAACUAAGGAUUGUUGAAGUUAAUUAUAACAAGGGACCAUCCUCACCCUGUGUUUGCUUUGUUCCAUUAAACGUGCGUUUGGCCUAAUGAAGUCAGUGAAUGUUCCUCUUUUUUCUUUUUUGGUUUCUUUGACUGAUUUUUGGAUGAUAUAUGUUGCUUUAUUUCUCCCAUUUUCUUUGAUUACUGUGGACAAAGGAAAACACUGAGGCAAAAGUAGGUCGUCAAUCACAUUACUUUGACCCAGUUGUGCAGAACCCCUUUCUACCUGCAGGUGUUAAUUCCAAUUCAAUGCAAAUAUCCUUUUCAAUCCGGUCCAUUCUUGGAGAAGAAACCCAUUGUAAGAGCUGUCUUCUGUGGUUGGGAUAUUACUUUGUAAAGUAUUAAAGCACUAAACCAGUUUUUGCAAUAUGUAGUAAAUCUUGCUUUCAUUUUGGAAAACUUCCAGUAAUGACUACUGCACUUUUUAUAGAAGAAUUGUAUUUAAUUUCUUUCUUUUAUGAAAGAUUAUUUCAAGUAAAAAUAGCUCUGUAAUCUGUGUGACAUGGCUUCUCCAUUACCUGACACAGAGAGAAGCUUUGAUGCCUACUCAAUAAAAUUAACAUGUUUGUAAAGUA